GGAAGGAAGAGGAAGAGGGUCUGGGCGAUGGUGCAUCCGGGACGAGCCUCCAGAGACCAAGCGGGAUAGGUAAACCCGCCGCGCAGCUGGCGGGACGCUGGGCCAACGAGGUCUGGGGUCUUGGCGCGGAGUUCAUGGGCCGCCGGCCAGGCUUGUGCCAGUGGCUUUGGAUCCCUGGCCUGCUUCCCCCAACCCAGCCUCCAGACCAGCGCUGGCCUGCUCCACACACUCCGCAGCACCGUCCCGGGAACCGAGCGUCGGCGGGGAGGCCGCCUCUCCGCAGUAGGUCUCGGCGGGCCUGAUCCCUUGGAGGCGCGUGUGUGGCACACGCCCAGGAGGGGCUUGAUUUUUGUUGAUGUGUGUUGUGAAUAAGGAAAAUGCUCUUCGUUAAGCCAUAUUUGUGACUUCCGAUAUUUCACUAAUACUUUUCAAUCAAGAAAACAGCAUUGCUAACUUGCCUAUCACUUUAAAGUGGUAUUUGAAGGAUUUGUGUGAUACAAUUAUGACUUUGUAAUUAGGCACCCUAAAAACCUGAUCAGGCCUAUUGCUUACUUUCUUUGAUUCAUCUGUCUUCUCUGCUGUGAUCACCUUGUUCCUCCUGAUAUGGAAGGUGUGAUAAAGCGGAAUUGGGAAUAUAUAUGUAGCCAUGAUAAAGAAAAAACGAAGAUCCUAGGAGACAAAAAUGUUGAUCCCAAAUGUGAAGACAGUGAGAACAAGUUUGACUUUUCAGUGAUGUCCUAUAAUAUACUUUCACAAGAUUUACUGGAAGAUAACUCUCACCUUUAUAGACAUUGCCGGCGGCCAGUAUUACACUGGAGUUUUAGGUUUCCCAAUAUUCUGAAAGAAAUUAAACAUUUUGAUGCAGACGUACUUUGUUUGCAAGAAGUUCAAGAAGAUCAUUAUGGAGCAGAGAUCAGGCCAAGUUUGGAAUCACUGGGUUAUCACUGUGAAUAUAAGAUGCGGACAGGAAGGAAACCUGAUGGCUGUGCUAUUUGCUUCAAACAUUCCAAAUUUUCACUCUUGUCAGUGAACCCAGUGGAAUUCUUCCGCCCUGAUAUUUCUCUGUUGGACAGAGACAAUGUUGGAUUAGUUUUACUCUUACAGCCCAAAAUUCCAUAUGCUGCCUGCCCUGCAAUCUGCGUAGCAAAUACGCAUCUGUUGUAUAAUCCAAGGCGAGGUGAUAUUAAGCUGACGCAAUUGGCAAUGCUACUGGCAGAGAUUUCCAGUGUUGCCCACCAGAAAGAUGGCAGCUUCUGCCCUAUUGUUAUGUGUGGUGACUUUAAUUCUGUUCCUGGUUCUCCACUAUAUAGUUUCAUAAAGGAAGGAAAAUUGAAUUAUGAAGGACUUCCCAUAGGAAAGGUAUCUGGCCAGGAACAGUCUUCACGGGGACAAAGAAUUUUAUCUAUUCCAAUUUGGCCCCCAAACCUAGGUAUCUCACAGAACUGUGUGUAUGAGGUACAGCAGGUACCAAAAGUAGAAAAGACAGACAGUGAUCUGACACAAACACAGCUGAAGCAAACAGAGGUCCUAGUGACAGCUGAAAAAUUGUCUUCAAAUUUACAGCACCAUUUCAGUUUGUCAUCUGUUUAUUCACAUUACUUUCCUGACACUGGAAUUCCAGAAGUGACCACCUGUCAUUCCCGAAGUGCCAUAACUGUGGAUUAUAUUUUCUACUCUGCAGAAAAGGAAGAUGUUGCUGGGCACCCAGGAGCUGAAGUUGCUUUGGUUGGUGGCUUGAAACUUCUAGCUAGACUGUCACUUCUUACAGAACAAGACUUAUGGACUGUUAAUGGACUUCCAAACGAAAAUAACUCUUCAGAUCAUCUGCCUUUAUUGGCAAAGUUCAGACUUGAGCUCUGACUCUCUUUGAUCACAUACUAAUUUUCUUUCCAAUUUGUAUUGUUUUUCAAAGAAUGUAAAGUUCUUAAGUGUAUGCAUGUUGUUUAUUUUUGCACUGUGGAGAUUCUGAAGCGGUUAUGUUAGAUGCUUUGAAACUCCAUAUCAGAAGAAAUAACUUUAUAACAAUUUUUUUUAAUAAUGAAAAAUAUUUUCGUGACAAGUGAGCUCUAAAUUCUCUUUAUUGUAAAAGAGAUGUAAAGGUUUUAUAUUCUAAAUCCUAGUAAAAUUGACAGUGAUUUUUAAAUAUAAUGCAUCUUCCUUUGUCUGCUUAGUAAAAAAUUUCAUUUCAUAAUUUUGGCAAGCUCUGUAGUGGAUCCAAAGUAUCUUUGAGUUCUUGCAAACUACAAGUUGUUUCCUUUCCAGAAGGCUUGAUUUCAUUAGGAGACCCCUCUAUUGAGUUCUAAAUAGUUUAUCUUAGAAAGCCUUGGGUCAUUCACAGGUAUCCAACCAGCCAUUGUUUAGUUUGUUUUUGAAGGGGUUUGAUAAUGCUUUUUAAGUUGUACAGAAUGCUUAAUCCAUCUUAUUACUGUCCUGAGCCAUGUAAUAUGCCUGCAUCGUGUUGGGGAAAUGUUUGGGAAAUAUAAGCCAGCAUAACGUGUAAAGCUCACUCUUUCACCCUGGAACAGACAAGAGGUGGGCUUAAUAGAGGCAGAGACUGGGGAUAUACCUUUGUUUCCCUAGCAUUUUUAUUUAUUUAUUUUUAUUUUAUUUUAUUUUUUGAGAUGGAGUUUCACUCUUGUUGCCCAGGCUGGGGGUGCAAUGGCGCAAUCUUUGCUCACUGCAACCCCUGCCUCCCGGGCUCAAGCGAUUCUCCUGCCUCAGCCUCUCGAGUAGCUGGGAUUACAGGCAUGCGUCACCACUCCCAGCUAAUUUUGUAUUUUCAGUAGAGACAGGGUUUCCCCAUGUUGGUUAGGCUGGUCUCGAACUCCCAACCUCAGGUGAUCCGCCCACCUCAGCUCUCAAAGUGCUGGGAUUACAGGCGGGAGCCACUGCACAUGGCAGCAUUUUUUAAAAAUUCAGUUUUAAGAUCUCUGGUUUAGGGGAGAGAUUUUAUUUUACUGAACCAGUUCUAUAGAAAUUUAUUUUAUUAGGAAAUUUGUCUUUGGAACAAAGUGGCAGCUAUAAAAUUAUUUUUGUUAAGCCUCAGAAAUAUGAGGAAGCCUGUAAAACUCUAGUGGGGAGAUAUUAACUUGGAGACCUAAUGCUCUGUAAAUAGUCAUUUAAACUGUUGGUUUUAGUGGUUUUGUUUCUAAAAUGUUUUCUUUUACCGUGAUGCACCAGUAUGAGAUGGUGCUGACACUUUCUAUGAAGUGGUUAUGAGCAGGUUUAAUAAAUCCUCUAUACAAGUGUUUGAAUCAAUUUUAAAACAUAAAAAGUGGAAAUUUCCUUUUUUGUAGACAGUAGGAACAAGGAAUUAUAUGCAUUUUUACUAAGUAGUAAUUUUACACUGAAUUGUAAAUGUUUUUACAGUGAGUUUUAUUAAUAGAAUGCUUCACCUUAAAUUGGAAAACAAUAAUAGUCUUGGACUAAGUCUUUGUACUAAAGCAUUUGCUAUAAUUAUUUUUAAAAAAACAAACAGAUGAAAACCUCAGAGAAGGCAUGUGGAUUAUAAGAUUUGUCUAGUAAAAAUUGUAAUUGAAUAUGUUUAAAUAUUUAAUUUCUCAUUUUGGGGGGUUUUUAUUUUUUUAUUUUUUAGAUGGUGUCUCACGCUAUCGCCCAGGCUGGAGUGCAGUGGCGCGAACUCGGCUCACUGCAACCUCCGCCUCCUGGGUUCAAGCAAUUCUCCUUCCUCAGCCUCCCAAGUAGCUGGGAUUACAGGCAUGCACCACCAUGCCCAGCUAAUUUUUGUAUUUUUAGUAGAGAUGGAAUUUUGCCAUGUUGGCCAGGCUGGUCUUGAACUCCUGACCUCAGGGGUGAUCCACCCGCCUCGGGCUCCCAAAGUGCUGUGAUUACAGGCAUGAGCCACCAUGCCUGGCCUUUGGGGGGAUUUUAAUUACAGUAUUAAUUAUAGUUCUAGGAUUUCCCACAUUUUAUAGUAGUAGUUUGCAGGAUAUUAUGUGCCCUAAUUAGCAGAUAUAGACAUUAUCAAAUUAUAAUGAUAGUAUAAUUAUCCCUUUUUAAUAUUGGGGAAAGAAAAAUGAAAAUUCAUUAGUUAAUUACUGCUUUGUGUUGUGUGAAUUUAUUAACAAAUAACAUUAUUACAUAUAGGUCAUUGUUAACAAACAAACAUCCCUGAAAACCUCUGUGAAAAUUUAAUUUUUUAUAUCCUGAUUAAUAUAUUGUGACUUUAGGCCCAUUUUUCAUGUGCUUCACUUUGAUAGAGUUAAUCCAUAAAAUUGCUCUUUACUUUAGCUUAUCAAAUGAAGUAUUAUUUUGUGGACUGGAGGCCAAAAAGUCAAUGUGAGCUUCUCACAGGUUUUUAAAGCUCCACUAAAAAUAAUUAUCCACUUGUCUUUACUUUUGUUGACCAGAAUAGUUGGUAACUCUGCCAGAGCCUGUACUUACCUGCCAAAAACAAUUAAAUCUGGUUAAUGCCUGAAACCAAAUCUCUCAGUCUCAAGUGUUAUACUAUCCAAGUUUUAAAUGGAAAGGUAAACUGUGGAGUAAUGAAAUUUUGGUUUUACUGUACCUUUUGCUAUCAAGAUAAUAUUCAUGUUUGAAAUCUUGUCUUUAUUUGGAAUUUAGUUACUGUCUGCUUUUAACCUUUGCUUUCCUAAAGAAAGUUUGAGAUCCAGAGAGUUCAAGGGAUUGGGGAAAGAGAGGCGUCAAGUCAUUUGCACUUUGUACCUGUAAGUUAGGUAAUAAACUAUUAUACUCGUA